CUUCUACCUGUGCGGCCCUCAACGUCUCCUUGGUGCGGGACCCGCUUCACUUUCGGCUCCCGGAGUCUCCCUCCACUGCUCAGACCUCUGGACCUGACAGGAGACGCCUACUUGGCUCUGACGCGGCGCCCCAGCCCGGCUGUGUCCCCGGCGCCCCGGACCACCCUCCCUGCCGGCUUUGGGUGCGUUGUGGGGUCCCGAGGAUUCGCGAGGUAAGGCCGCCCUCGCGUUGUUUGGUCUCAGGCUGCAGACCAGGUCAGGCGACUCUUGCAGUUUCUCCAGCUUGCCUGGUGCGUGCUGGUGUCUCGCCGCUUGGUCCUCUCCUGUUCUUCGGCCCCCGGUUGCCAGAUUGCUUUUCUUCCAGGCCUCAACCAGAUUUGUUGAAAGACAUUCAAGAUUACGAAGUUUAGAUGACCAAAAUGGAUAUCCGAGGUGCUGUGGAUGCUGCUGUCCCCACCAAUAUUAUUGCUGCCAAGGCUGCAGAAGUUCGUGCAAACAAAGUCAACUGGCAAUCCUAUCUUCAGGGACAGAUGAUUUCUGCUGAAGAUUGUGAGUUUAUUCAGAGGUUUGAAAUGAAACGAAGCCCUGAAGAGAAGCAAGAGAUGCUUCAAACUGAAGGCAGCCAGUGUGCUAAAACAUUUAUAAAUCUGAUGACUCAUAUCUGCAAAGAACAGACCGUUCAGUAUAUACUAACUAUGGUGGAUGAUAUGCUGCAGGAAAAUCAUCAGCGUGUUAGCAUUUUCUUUGACUAUGCAAGAUGUAGCAAGAACACUGCGUGGCCCUACUUUCUGCCAAUGUUGAAUCGCCAGGAUCCCUUCACUGUUCAUAUGGCAGCAAGAAUUAUUGCCAAGUUAGCAGCUUGGGGAAAAGAACUGAUGGAAGGCAGUGACUUAAAUUACUAUUUCAAUUGGAUAAAAACUCAGCUGAGUUCACAGAAACUGCGUGGUAGCGGUGUUGCUGUUGAAACAGGAACAGUCUCUUCAAGUGAUAGUUCGCAGUAUGUGCAGUGCGUGGCCGGGUGUUUGCAGCUGAUGCUCCGGGUCAAUGAGUACCGCUUUGCUUGGGUGGAAGCAGAUGGGGUAAAUUGCAUAAUGGGAGUGUUGAGUAACAAGUGUGGCUUUCAGCUCCAGUAUCAAAUGAUUUUUUCAAUAUGGCUCCUGGCAUUCAGUCCUCAAAUGUGUGAACACCUGCGGCGCUAUAAUAUCAUUCCAGUUCUGUCUGAUAUCCUUCAGGAGUCUGUCAAAGAGAAAGUAACAAGAAUCAUUCUUGCAGCAUUUCGUAACUUUUUAGAAAAAUCAACUGAAAGAGAAACUCGCCAAGAAUAUGCCCUGGCUAUGAUUCAGUGCAAAGUUCUGAAACAGUUGGAGAACUUGGAACAGCAGAAGUACGAUGAUGAAGAUAUCAGCGAAGAUAUCAAAUUUCUUUUGGAAAAACUUGGAGAGAGUGUCCAGGACCUUAGUUCAUUUGAUGAAUACAGUUCAGAACUUAAAUCUGGAAGGUUGGAAUGGAGUCCUGUGCACAAAUCUGAGAAAUUUUGGAGAGAGAAUGCUGUGAGGUUAAAUGAGAAGAAUUAUGAACUCUUGAAAAUCUUGACAAAACUUUUGGAAGUGUCAGAUGAUCCCCAAGUCUUAGCUGUUGCUGCUCACGAUGUUGGAGAAUAUGUGCGGCAUUAUCCACGAGGCAAACGGGUCAUCGAGCAGCUCGGUGGGAAGCAGCUGGUCAUGAACCACAUGCAUCAUGAAGACCAGCAGGUCCGCUAUAAUGCUCUGCUGGCCGUGCAGAAGCUCAUGGUGCACAACUGGGAAUACCUUGGCAAGCAGCUCCAGUCCGAGCAGCCCCAGACCGCUGCCGCCCGAAGCUAAGCCUGCCUCUGGCCUUCCCCUCCGCCUCAAUGCAGAACCAGUAGUGGGAGCACUGUGUUUAGAGUUAAGAGUGAACACUGUUUGAUUUUACUUGGAAUUUCCUCUGUUAUAUAGCUUUUCCCAAUGCUAAUUUCCAAACAACAACAACAAAAUAACAUGUUUGCCUGUUAAGUUGUAUAAAAGUAGGUGAUUCUGUAUUUAAAGAAAAUAUUACUGUUACAUAUACUGCUUGCAAUUUCUGUAUUUAUUGUUCUCUGGAAAUAAAUAUAGUUAUUAAAGGAUUCUCACUCCAAACAUGGCCUCUCUCUUUACUUGGACUUUGAACAAAAGUCAACUGUUGUCUCUUUUCAAACCAAAUUGGGAGAAUUGUUGCAAAGUAGUGAAUGGCAAAUAAAUGUUUUAAAAUCUAUCGCUCUAUCAA